AGUCACAGCCAGGUAACCCUGGAGUGAAGCGGUUUAGUUAGAAGGGAGCAGAUAAACUCGUCACUCUAGUAGCUUUAACCCUCACCCUGAGGCACCUUAGCAAUCAGCCAUUGCCUGCAAGCCUCCAAAGCUUGUCUUUGCCUAAUAUGGAGCCCAAAGAAGCCACUGGGAAAGAAAACAUGGUCACCAAGAAAAAGAAUCUGGCCUUCUUGAGGUCUAGACUCUAUAUGCUGGAGAGAAGGAAGACUGACACUGUGGUUGAGAGCAGUGUUUCUGGGGACCACUCUGGCACCUUGAGGAGGAGCCAAUCUGACAGGACCGAAUACAACCAGAAAUUACAAGAAAAGAUGACUCCACAGGGUGAGUGUUCUGUAGCUGAGACCUUAACCCCAGAGGAAGAGCAUCAUAUGAAGAGGAUGAUGGCAAAGCGGGAAAAGAUCAUUAAGGAGCUGAUACAGACAGAAAAGGAUUAUCUCAAUGAUCUAGAGCUGUGUGUUAGGGAAGUGGUUCAGCCCCUGAGAAAUAAAAAGACUGAUAGGCUGGAUGUGGAUAGCUUGUUUAGCAACAUUGAGUCCGUGCAUCAGAUAUCAGCCAAGCUGCUGUCAUUGUUGGAAGAGGCCACAACAGACGUGGAACCGGCCAUGCAAGUAAUUGGAGAAGUAUUCUUGCAGAUUAAAGGGCCACUGGAAGAUAUUUAUAAAAUCUACUGCUAUCACCAUGAUGAAGCACAUAGUAUACUGGAGUCCUAUGAAAAGGAAGAAGAGCUGAAGGAACAUUUGAGCCACUGUAUCCAGUCCUUAAAGAAAAUAUACAUGCAAGAAGGCAAACCAAACUUAUUGGACAUGGGCUCUUUGAUGAUCAAACCAAUUCAACGUGUGAUGAAAUACCCCCUAUUACUGUGCGAACUUCGGAAUUCCACCCCUCCCUCUCACCCAGAUUACAGAGCACUGGACGAUGCCUUUGCUGCUGUGAAGGACAUUAAUGUUAACAUCAAUGAACUUAAAAGAAGGAAAGAUUUAGUUCUAAAAUACAAGAAGAAUGACGAGGAUGAAUCACUUAAAGACAAAUUGUCUAAACUAAAUAUUCAUUCAAUUAGCAAGAAAUCAAAAAGAGUGACAAAUCAUCUGAAGAUUCUGACCAGAGGAGAAUCACAGGUUAAAGACAAUACCUUUAACAGAGAAGAAAAGCUGUUUAGAGCUUUAGAAAAGACUGUGAGGCUUUGUGUGAAGAACAUUUCACUCUGUCUUCAACACAUACAGGAUGCCAUGCCCCUGGCUCUGCAGAGUGUGAUGGACCUUCAGGAGAUUUCAUACAACAAAGACGAUGAGAUGGACUAUUCUGAGACCCUAAGUAAUGCCUUAAAUUCGUGUCAUGACUUUGCAUCUCACUUACAGAGACUCAUCCUGACCCCCUUGUCAGCCCUGCUGUCCUUAUUCCCAGGGCCUCACAAGCUCAUCCAGAAACGCUAUGACAAACUGCUGGAUUGCAACAGCUACCUGCAGCGAUCAACGGGAGAGGAGUCAGACUUGGCCAAAAAGGAGUAUGAGGCCCUCAACGCCCAGCUUGUGGAGGAGCUCCAGGCAUUCAACCAGGCUGCUCGGAAGAUUCUGUUGAACUGUCUAUGCAGCUUCAUUACCCUCCUUAGGGACCUGAUGCUCGUGGCACAGCAGGCUUACUCCACACUUGUGCCGAUGCCACUGUUGGUUUCAAGCAUUUCUGAGAUUCAGAAUCAAGUACUAGAAGAGAUCCAAAAUUUGAAUUGUGUGAAAGAAAACAGUGCCACCUUUAUUGAGAGGAAACUCAGUUUUGAAAAGAAGAAACCUGUGCAGAUUCUGCCAGAAAUGCCACAUCAAACUGACAUUCAUCGCUCCAAACUUCUAUCCACAUAUAGUGCAGAGGAACUCUAUCAAGCUAAGCGCAAGUGCAAUGCUACACAAGAAUAUGACAUCAAUCUUCUGGAAGGAGACUUGGUGGCUGUGAUAGAACAGAAAGAUCCACUGGGGAGUACAAGCAGGUGGCUUGUGGACACAGGAAAUGUGAAAGGAUAUGUUUAUUCCUCCUUCCUAAAACCCUACAAUCCAGCAAAAAUGCAGAAAGUGGAUGCUGAGAACAGGUUCUGUGACGAUGAUUUUGAGAACAUCAGCCUCUUCGUGUCUUCACGGCCAGCUAGUGACAGUGUCACAGGCACCUCAGAAAGCAGCAUUGGUGAUAGCAGCUCAUCUCUUAGUGGCACAUGUGGAAAGUUUGAAACAAAUGGUACUGAUGUUGACAGUUUUCAAGAAGUAGACGAACAGAUUUUCUAUGCAGUUCAUGCUUUUCAAGCACGGAGUGACCAUGAACUCAGCCUUCAGGAAUACCAGAGAGUUCAUAUACUCAGGUUUUGUGACCUAAGUGGCAAUAAAGAGUGGUGGUUAGCUGAAGCUCAAGGGCAGAAAGGAUACGUGCCAGCUAACUACCUUGGAAAGAUGACUUAUGCUUAAGAAAAUAAGCCUUCAACUUUUAUUUUCCAGCAAGUUGUUGAUUGACUACCUCAUAAAACUGACAUUACAAAACUUUGGACCAGAAAGCAAGAAACCUCUGAACUACAGAAACUGAUACUGUACUGGGUUUUCAGGAAUACUGUACUUCCUAACAGGAUUAUUGCAUGAAUGUAUUAUAAAGGAUACAUGUUGAAAGAAAUACUAAGCCAACAGAAAUAGCAAAGCAAAUGACCCAAGCUUCAACUAUCAACUAUUUAAAAGUGAAGAUCUUUUGAAGGAGUAAUUAUAUUCUUUUAUCAUCAAGAAAGGUUGGAUCCAAAGGUUUUUCAAUUUACUUUUUUUUUUACUGUAUGAUGUAUUUUGCCUUAAAUGUUUUUGUUUUUCAUAUUGCUCUCUUGCAAAUGCAUACAUGUUUAUAUACAUACAUAUAAACCAUAUAUAUUAUGUAGCUUUAUACACGUAUGUGGAUAAUAUGAAUUAUACACCUAUAUGUAUAAAUCAGAGUAUACACCAAAUAUACAUAAGAAGAAUAUACCACCAACUAGAAGUCUUUGAUAAUAUAUUUUGUUAAUGUUUCGUUUAUAUGUUUUGAACUAAAACUGAAUAACUUGAUAUUAACAUGUAACAUUACUGAAUGCACACUAUAUGCCAGACAUUGUUCUAAGUGCUUUAUAUGUAGUAACUUGUUUAAUAUUCAAAACAUUAUGAAGAAACCAUGGCCCAAAAAGGUGAAGUAAUUUAAUCCAAAUCACAUUGCUAUUAAGUGGUGGGCCUGGACUUAAACCUAGGUAGUGUAAACCAAAAAUAAAAUUCUAAGGCUUCCAACCAUCUAAAUAGACUUCCCCUUCAGCCAGGGCUUUUUUCUUUCUUUUCUUGUUGUUUUUUUUUUUUUUUAAAGAGACAAUAAAAGGAGGUUUUUUUAUUCAAAGGUAUAACUGGAUAAGUAGAUUUGUUUACAAUCAUUCUUGUGAAAUACUUUUUUAAAAAAAUACGAUCAACUUCUUUGCAAAUAGUAGACACAUACCUCAACAAUGAUGACCUAAUUUUUGAUCCAUAAUGUAAGAUUAGGUAGAAAUAGGCAAGCUCACACUGCUAAAUUAACUAUCAAAUACUCAGUCAAAACUCCAUUUGUGGCCCCCACUUCUUGAUCUAUUUCUGUUCCACUUCGUCUUCUACCAUCUUGCCGACUUUCCUGAGCAACUGCUUUGUCGACUCUCUCUACCUGACCAAUUGCCAGAUCGACAACCUGACUGGCCUGACCAGCCACUCCUCUGUCUGGAAUUAAAAGAUGUUUCCAUCAUAAUAUUCUUUAAUUUCAGGUAAUUUAGCUGGCACUGAGAGUAUCCAGCCGGAAUCAUGCCACUUUGCCUGUAACCUUUGACUCAAUUGGAGGAAUAUCAAAGCAAACACCCAUAUUUCCUUUCAGGAGGCACACUCUGGUAAUCUGAGACACUGCAUUACUAUUCAGCUUUCUAAGUUCUUUCCAAGCACAGCUGACAUCCUGUAUUUCCUCUAGGCUUUCCAGAGUCAUGGUCACAAACCCCUUAUCAGAGUUGAUUAAAGAUCAUGGUUCAAAGCUUGAUACACCAGAAAUGUGGGCUAAAGCUGCAGCCAAUGCAUCUAUCGCCCCUUUCUCUUCUAUCAGUAUCUGAGCUGAUGGUUGGAAAAAAAUCAACAGCAGCAUAAGAAAUGGAAGCCAGAGACCUUAUGGCAUCCAUGCUUUUAAAUUUAACUAAAUCCAUUGUAGAAGGAACACCUACACAUUUAAAAGUAAUUUGUGUUUUUUGUUCCACAUGUCUUAGUUGACCUUUCUCUUGGUUGAUAAAAACAUAUACAAACCCCUGUCUGUCCAGCUUUACCCACGCAUCCAGAGAGAUGGAUAUAGGACUCAAUAUCCUGAGGAGGAGAACUUUGAAUCACCAGGUCAACUACAGGAAUGUCCAAACCACGAGGAGCCACAUUGGUUGCCACCAAAACUUUAUAAUUACCUCUCUGAAGCCUUUUAGUGUAAUUUCUCUUUGUGACUGUGCAAUGUCCCCAUGUAAACACAGUGCAUUCUGUUUUGUGCGGAUUCAUGGCCAUGUCAGUUACAUUCUUCUUCGUCUCACAGAAAAUAAUAGCCCUCCCUUCAGAUCCACUGUAGACUUGAAGGACAUCUCAUUUUCAUCUGUGUUUUAUAAAGGAGGAAAUUGAGGACCUCACAUGGAGGGACUGGAAUUUAAAACCAGGUCUUCUGACUUUAAGGCCUUUCUUUUAGUGUUUUCCCUUUUCUUUUCCUUAAGUCACUAAAAUCUGUAGUUAUAUAAUCUUACAUAAAGCAUAUGCAAAAUAGAAAAAUGAUAGUCACCACAUAUCUACUAAUGGGAUUAAAAUGUACAAUCCUAAAAGCUUACUUGUUAGCACACUUGCUUAUCUGUCCAUUCAUUCAUUGAACCAGUAAGUAUUUAUUGAGAGUUAGUGGGAAUACAAUGCUGUGCAAGACAAACAAGAUCCCUCCAUUCAUACCACUUAAAUUCUAGUGGGGAAAACAUCUGCACAUAACAAACUAAAUAAAAUGAUCAUAAAAUAAUAAAUGCUAUUUAUAUAAAACUGGCUACUUUCAUUACUGCUCAGUUAAAGGGUCUUGUAGCUCAUUUUAUGACAUGAAAAAAAUCAAGGUCUAAAAGCUCCUUGAGACAAUUUAAACUCUAAUACCAAAUAUACCUCUAUAAAAUACCAAACUGAGCUAAAUACGGUAUAUGUGUACUUAUACAUAUGUACAUAACCUAAAUAUACGUGUGCACACAUUAUCUAUACAAAGAGCCAUACUCAGUGAAAGAUAAAUUACCUCCUAAACUAAAGUCCCCUCUGAGGUACAACAGAAAUUAAAAUAAUUGCUUCUCUUCUCAACUCUAUGUAGCACGUAUUUUCCAUGAUGGGAUAAAUGUUUUCAUUUCAAGUGCCAAUGUGUGAACUGUAAUAAACAUUACUGCUUUCA